GCGGGGACCGGGCGGGCCGGGCGCUGGGAGCUGGCUGUCCCAGGAGCAGAGCAGUCUCCCUGUCCAGAUCACCAGGAUCCCUGCUUGCUGGAGAAUGACCCAGAUGUCCCAGGUGCAGGAGCUCUUCCAUGAGGCAGCCCAGCAGGAUGCCCUGGCCCAGCCCCAGCCCUGGUGGAAGACCCAGCUGUUCAUGUGGGAGCCUGUGCUGUUUGGGACCUGGGAUGGUGUGUUCACAUCCUGCAUGAUCAACAUCUUUGGGGUUGUGCUCUUCCUGAGGACUGGCUGGCUGGUGGGAAACACAGGAGUGCUCCUGGGCAUGUUCCUGGUGUCCUUCGUCAUCCUGGUGGCCCUCGUCACGGUGCUGUCUGGCAUUGGCGUCGGGGAGCGCAGCAGCAUCGGCAGCGGUGGCGUCUACUCCAUGAUCUCCUCGGUCCUGGGUGGGCAGACGGGAGGCACCAUCGGGCUGCUCUAUGUGUUUGGACAGUGUGUUGCAGGUGCCAUGUAUAUCACCGGCUUUGCUGAAUCCAUCUCGGAUUUGCUGGGCCUCGGGAAUAUCUGGGCUGUGCGAGGAAUUUCAGUUGCGGUGCUUCUGGCCUUGCUGGGCAUUAACCUCGCAGGUGUCAAAUGGAUAAUCCGCCUCCAGCUGCUGUUGCUGUUCCUGCUGGCCGUGUCCACACUGGACUUUGUGGUGGGUUCUUUCACCCACCUGGACCCAGAACAUGGUUUCAUUGGAUAUUCACCCGAACUGCUACAGAACAACACGCUGCCCGAUUACAGCCCGGGGGAAUCUUUUUUCACUGUCUUUGGGGUUUUCUUCCCAGCGGCUACAGGAGUCAUGGCCGGCUUCAACAUGGGGGGCGACCUCAGGGAGCCUGCCGCCAGCAUUCCCCUGGGCUCCCUGGCAGCUGUUGGCAUCUCGUGGUUUCUGUACAUCAUCUUCGUCUUCCUCCUGGGCGCCAUCUGCACUCGAGAGGCCCUUCGCUAUGACUUCCUGAUAGCGGAAAAGGUAUCCCUCAUGGGCUUCCUGUUCCUUUUGGGCUUAUACAUCUCGUCCCUGGCUUCCUGCAUGGGAGGACUUUAUGGAGCUCCCCGCAUCCUGCAGUGCAUUGCCCAGGAGAAAGUGAUCCCUGCACUUGCCUGUCUGGGACAAGGGAAGGGGCCAAACAAAACACCCGUGGCUGCCAUCUGCCUGACCAGCUUGGUGACCAUGGCCUUUGUUUUUGUGGGUCAAGUGAACGUUCUGGCCCCCAUCGUCACCAUCAACUUCAUGCUGACAUACGUUGCAGUGGACUACUCUUACUUCUCCCUGUCCAUGUGUUCCUGCAGCCUGACCCCGGUGCCUGAGCCGGUGCUCAGGGAGGGCGCAGAAGGCCUCCACUGCUCUGAGCACCUGCUCUUAGAGAAAGCUCCCAGUUACGGCUCUGAGGGACCUGCCCAAAGAGUCUUGGAGGGCACGCUACUGGAAUUCACCAAGGACAUGGAUCAGCUCCUCCAGCUAACCAGGAAGCUUGAGAGUAGCCAGCCCAGGCAAGGAGAGGGUAACAGGACCCCAGAAAGUCAGAAGAGGAAAAGCAAGAAGGCCACCAAGCAGACCCUACAAGAUAGCUUCCUCUUGGACCUCAAAUCCCCUCCUUCUUUCCCUGUCGAGAUCUCUGACAGGUUGCCCGCUGCCUCCUGGGAGGGGCAGGAGUCCUGCUGGAACAAGCAGACUUCCAAGAGCGAAGGGACUCAGCCUGAGGGAACAUAUGGAGAGCAACUUGUUCCUGAGCUGUGCAACCAAUCAGAGUCCAGUGGAGAAGAUUUCUUCCUGAAGUCCAGGCUCCAAGAACAAGAUGUCUGGAGAAGAUCCACUUCUUUCUAUACCCACAUGUGCAACCCCUGGGUCUCCCUGUUGGGGGCUGUUGGGUCCCUUCUCAUCAUGUUUGUGAUACAGUGGGUGUAUACCCUGGUUAACAUGGGUGUUGCUGCCAUCGUGUAUUUCUACAUUGGCCGGGCCAGUCCAGGGCUUCACCUUGGAUCAGCCUCCAACUUCAGCUUUUUCCGGUGGAUGAGGUCUCUCUUGCUCCCCUCCUGCAGGAGCUUGCGGUCCCCUCAGGAGCAGAUCAUCUUGGCGCCGUCCCUGGCUAAGGUUGACAUGGAGAUGACUCAGCUCACCCAGGAGAAUGCAGACUUCGCCACUCGGGAUCGCUACCACCACUCCUCCCUCGUGAACCGGGAGCAGCUGAUGCCUCACUACUAGAUGCAGUGCUGGGACCUUCCUCUUUUGGAGCUGUCCCAUGUACAGUGGACCCAAGCUCAGGACCUUCGUGGAGCUGCUUCUCCAACCUGAGAAACUCAAGACCCAUCCUCCCGCUGUCACUUUGGACAAUGGAAAUCUACAUUUUCUUUUCCCUUUUUUUUUUUUUUUGAGACAGAGUCUCGCCCUGUCACCCAGGCUGGAGUCCAGUGGCACAAUCUUGGCUCACUGCAACCUCUGCUUCCCGAGUUCAAGCAAUUCUCCUGCCUCAGCCUCCUGAGUAGCUGGGAUUAUAGGCAUGCACCACCACACCCAGCUAUUUUUUGUAUUUUUACUGGAGACAGGGUUUCACCAUGUUGGCCAGGCUGGUCUCGAACUCCUGACCUCGUGAUCCACCCGUCUCAGCCUCCCAAAGUACUGGGAUUACAGGCGUGAGCCACCAUGCCUGGCCAGAAAUCUAUGUUUUCUUAGAACAUGUGGAAGAAGGAAAAAGACAAAAAAGGAAAUCUGGAUUCUGAGGACCACGUCUCACCCAGGGUGACAUCAGGAAUGGUGCUAGCCUCUGCAACACGACACCCAGUCUGAAGAGCUCUAUACAGGUACUAAGACUAGCAGGGGACACCAAGACUCUGCACAACCAGAUUGCUUGUGCAGAGGGCCACAAUAAGUGUAUGUUUUAUAUUUUAUUGUAUUAUUUAUUCAAAAAUAAAUAAUACACUCACAUGUUUCCACACCCAAAAGAUAUAUAGAGUGAAAAGUCUCCCUCCAAUCCUUAUUCUCCACCUGCUCAGUUCCUGUCUACCCUGGCCUAGAGGUAACCACUAUUCUCAUCCGUACAUCCAGCAUUUCUUUAUGGAUAUACAAGCAAAUGGGAAUGUAGAGUCUCACAUUCUCUCUUUAUACACAAAAGUUAGCACGUUAUACACAUGUUCUGCACCUUGCUUUUUUCCCUUAACAAUCUAUCUUGGAGACAUUUCAUAUCAAUUCAUAUGCCAUUUGUUCAUUUUUUUCAUUGUAUAAAUGUGUUAUAAUUUAUUUCGCCAGUUCCACAAUGAUGAGCAUUUGGAUUCUUUCCAAUCUUUUGCAAUGACAAUCAGCUCUGCAGUGAAUAAUCUUGUACAAAUGUGCAAGCAUAAAGUGUAUCUCUAGGAUAAAUUCCCAAAAGUGGAAUUGCAGGAUCAAAAGGUACAUGCAUUUGUAAACUAUUAUUGUUUAGUGAGGGUCUUUUUAAUUAAAGAAUUAACAUGAA